GCUCUAUUCCAGAGACCGAGUGGCAGGGCGGCCACUGUGGCGGGGCUCUUUCCCCGUUUCGCCUCAGCUACCCCUCAGCUCCGGUAGUCGCCAGUCCGGGGUCGUCGCCGUUUGGGGCGGGAGCUGCUCGGCCCCGCCGCCGUCCCCGUCGCCGCUUCCGGGUCCAGGCCCCUCGGGCCGCCUGCCGCCGUCAUGAGGCUGCGGGUGCGGCUUCUGAAGCGGACCUGGCCGCUGGAGGUGCCCGAGACGGAGCCGACGCUGGGGCAUUUGCGCUCGCACCUGAGGCAGUCCCUGCUGUGCACCUGGGGGUACAGUUCUAAUACCCGAUUUACAAUUACAUUGAACUACAAGGAUCCCCUCACUGGAGAUGAAGAGACCUUGGCUUCAUAUGGGAUUGUUUCUGGGGACUUGAUAUGUUUGAUUCUUCAAGAUGACAUUCCAGCGCCUAAUAUACCUUCAUCCACAGAUUCAGAGCAUUCUUCACUCCAGAAUAAUGAGCAACCCUCUUUGGCCACCAGCUCCAAUCAGACUAGCAUGCAGGAUGAACAACCAAGUGAUUCAUUCCAAGGACAGGCAGCCCAGUCUGGUGUUUGGAAUGACGACAGUAUGUUAGGGCCUAGUCAAAAUUUUGAAGCUGAGUCAAUUCAAGAUAAUGCGCAUAUGGCAGAGGGCACAGGUUUCUAUCCCUCAGAACCCAUGCUCUGUAGUGAAUCGGUGGAAGGGCAAGUGCCACAUUCAUUAGAGACCUUGUAUCAAUCAGCUGACUGUUCUGAUGCCAAUGAUGCCUUGAUAGUGUUGAUACAUCUUCUCAUGUUGGAGUCAGGUUACAUACCUCAGGGCACCGAAGCCAAAGCACUGUCCAUGCCGGAGAAGUGGAAGUUGAGCGGGGUGUAUAAGCUGCAGUACAUGCAUCCUCUCUGCGAGGGCAGCUCCGCUACUCUCACCUGUGUGCCUUUGGGAAACCUGAUUGUUGUAAAUGCUACACUAAAAAUCAACAAUGAGAUUAGAAGUGUGAAAAGAUUGCAGCUGCUACCAGAAUCUUUUAUUUGCAAAGAGAAACUAGGGGAAAAUGUAGCCAACAUAUACAAAGAUCUUCAGAAACUCUCUCGCCUCUUUAAAGACCAGCUGGUGUAUCCUCUUCUGGCUUUUACCCGACAAGCACUGAACCUACCAGAUGUAUUUGGGUUGGUCGUCCUCCCAUUGGAACUGAAACUACGGAUCUUCCGACUUCUGGAUGUUCGUUCCGUCUUGUCUUUGUCUGCGGUUUGUCGUGACCUCUUUACUGCUUCAAAUGACCCACUCCUGUGGAGGUUUUUAUAUCUGCGUGAUUUUCGAGACAAUACUGUCAGAGUUCAAGACACAGAUUGGAAAGAACUGUACAGGAAGAGGCACAUACAAAGAAAAGAAUCCCCGAAAGGGCGGUUUGUGAUGCUCCUGCCAUCGUCAACUCACACCAUUCCAUUCUAUCCCAACCCCUUGCACCCUAGGCCAUUUCCUAGCUCCCGCCUUCCUCCAGGAAUUAUCGGGGGUGAAUAUGACCAAAGACCAACACUUCCCUAUGUUGGAGACCCAAUCAGUUCACUCAUUCCUGGUCCUGGGGAGACGCCCAGCCAGUUUCCUCCACUGAGACCACGCUUUGAUCCAGUUGGCCCACUUCCAGGACCUAACCCCAUCUUGCCAGGGCGAGGCGGCCCCAAUGACAGAUUUCCCUUUAGACCCAGCAGGGGUCGGCCAACUGAUGGCCGGCUGUCAUUCAUGUGAUUGAUUUGUAAUUUCAUUUCUGGAGCUCCAUUUGUUUUUGUUUCUAAACUACAGAUGUCAACUCCUUGGGGUGCUGAUCUCGAGUGUUAUUUUCUGAUUGUGGUGUUGAGAGUUGCACUCCCAGAAACCUUUUAAGAGAUACAUUUAUAGCCCUAGGGGUGGUAUGACCCAAAGGUUCCUCUGUGACAAGGUUGGCCUUGGGAAUAGUUGGCUGCCAAUCUCCCUGCUCUUGGUUCUCCUCUAGAUUGAAGUUUGUUUUCUGAUGCUGUUCUUACCAGAUUAAAAAAAAGUGUAAAUUA